GAAUGGGGUAGAAGGCCUGUUGUGGAGGGAAACCACCCAUCCUCCUGCCUCCCACCACCACCAUCAUCCUGGCUGGACGGAGAGGGUGACGGGGGCUGGGAAGGGGCAGCUCAUGUUCAGGUUUCCAGGAGGGGCUACCUGUUGACUGUCUUUGCAGGAAGAAGAAAACACCUGAGUGACCAGAUGUCCCAGCUCCAGGUGCCUUGCCAGAUGGCCAGAACCACACCUCUUGAAGAGUGACAGGUGCCAGUGUGCUGUGGAGCAUGGUUUCUGCACACCUGGAAUGACUGGAACCCCAAAGACUCAAGAAGGAGCUAAAGAUCUUGAAGUAGACAUGAAUAAAACAGAAGUUACUCCCAGGCUGUGGACCACCUGUCGAGAUGGAGAAGUCCUUCUGAGGCUAUCCAAACACGGACCAGGCCAUGAGACCCCGAUGACCAUCCCUGAAUUUUUUCGAGAGUCAGUCAACCGAUUUGGAACUUAUCCAGCCCUCGCAUCCAAGAAUGGCAAAAAGUGGGAAAUUCUGAAUUUCAACCAGUACUAUGAGGCUUGUCGGAAGGCUGCAAAAUCCUUGAUCAAGCUGGGUUUGGAGCGUUUCCACGGAGUUGGUAUCCUGGGGUUUAACUCUGCAGAGUGGUUUAUCACUGCUGUUGGUGCCAUCCUAGCCGGGGGUCUUUGUGUUGGUAUUUAUGCCACCAACUCUGCCGAGGUUUGUCAAUAUGUCAUCACUCAUGCCAAAGUGAACAUCUUGCUGGUUGAGAAUGAUCAACAGUUACAGAAAAUCCUUUCGAUUCCACAGAGCAGCCUAGAGCCCCUAAAAGCGAUCAUCCAGUACAGACUGCCAAUGAAGAAGAACAACAACUUGUACUCUUGGGAUGAUUUCAUGGAACUUGGCAGAAGUAUCCCUGACACCCAACUGGAGCAGGUCAUCGAGAGCCAGAAGGCGAAUCAAUGCGCAGUGCUCAUCUACACUUCAGGGACCACAGGCAUACCCAAGGGAGUGAUGCUCAGUCAUGACAACAUCACGUGGAUUGCAGGAGCAGUGACAAAGGACUUUAAACUGACAGACAAGCAUGAGACGGUGGUUAGCUACCUCCCACUCAGCCAUAUUGCAGCACAGAUGAUGGACAUCUGGGUACCCAUAAAGAUUGGGGCGCUCACAUACUUUGCUCAAGCAGAUGCUCUCAAGGGCACCUUGGUAAGUACUCUAAAGGAGGUAAAACCUACUGUCUUCAUUGGAGUGCCUCAAAUUUGGGAGAAGAUACAUGAGAUGGUGAAGAAAAAUAGUGCCAAGUCCAUGGGCUUGAAGAAGAAGGCAUUCGUGUGGGCAAGAAACAUUGGCUUCAAGGUCAACUCAAAAAAGAUGUUGGGGAAAUAUAAUACUCCCGUGAGCUACCGCAUGGCUAAGACUCUCGUGUUCAGCAAAGUCAAGACAUCCCUUGGCUUGGAUCACUGUCACUCUUUUAUCAGUGGGACUGCGCCCCUCAACCAAGAGACUGCCGAGUUCUUUCUAAGCUUGGACAUACCUAUAGGCGAGUUGUAUGGGUUGAGUGAGAGCUCGGGACCCCACACGAUAUCCAACCAGAAUAACUACAGGCUUCUAAGCUGUGGCAAGAUCUUGACUGGGUGUAAGAAUAUGCUGUUCCAGCAGAACAAGGAUGGCAUUGGGGAGAUCUGCCUCUGGGGUAGGCACAUCUUCAUGGGCUAUCUGGAAAGUGAGACUGAAACUACAGAGGCCAUCGAUGAUGAAGGCUGGCUACACUCUGGGGAUCUGGGCCAGCUGGACGGUCUGGGUUUCCUCUAUGUCACCGGCCACAUCAAAGAAAUCCUUAUCACUGCUGGUGGUGAAAAUGUGCCCCCCAUUCCUGUUGAGACCUUGGUUAAGAAGAAGAUCCCCAUCAUCAGUAACGCCAUGUUAGUAGGAGAUAAACUGAAGUUUCUGAGCAUGUUGCUGACGCUGAAGUGUGAGAUGAAUCAGAUGAGCGGAGAACCUCUGGACAAGCUGAACUUCGAGGCCAUCAACUUCUGUCGGGGUCUGGGCAGCCAGGCAUCCACCGUGACUGAGAUUGUGAAGCAGCAAGACCCCCUGGUCUACAAGGCCAUCCAGCAAGGCAUCAAUGCUGUGAACCAGGAAGCCAUGAACAAUGCACAGAGGAUUGAAAAGUGGGUCAUCUUGGAGAAGGACUUUUCCAUCUAUGGUGGAGAGCUAGGUCCAAUGAUGAAACUUAAGAGACAUUUUGUAGCCCAGAAAUACAAAAAACAAAUUGAUCACAUGUACCACUGACUGCUUUGAUGGAGCUGCUCUCAGCUGUUCUGAUGCCUUCAGCAGGAAGACCUCAUUGCAAUAAGUGAAAUGCUGCUCUAGGUAGAAGCUCUCCCUGCUGUUUUUAAGAAGCCACAUUCCUCAUUGGUCAGUUUCUUGAUUGUUCGUCUGUUGGAGAGGUGCUCCCUAGAAGAACCUGCCAUACGUUUCAAAGCAAUAAAAUCACUGUAUAUCUUUCUAAGGACCUUCAAGUCAUGACUCCAGGGAAGCCUAUUGGGAAGUCUACUAAAAACUGCCUGAUUUACAAGAAAGACCUGAACUUGUGGGCUCCCAUUUGAUUUUUUUCUCCUCAGGGGACUCAGACAUUAGAAAGAAAAAGCCUCACAGAUUUGAAGAACUGGACCCCCAAAUCAACUCACCUGCCUGGAAGCAACUGGGAAACCCUUCCAAUAAGUCCUGAUAAUAAAGCACUUCAGGGUC